AUGCUCCAGGUGGACCCCCUGGUUGUGAGGGGUGCCCGGCGAGCUCUGAGCCUGCCCACCAGGGCCAGUGAAGCUCCAGCCCAGCAGACAUCCAGUCUCUCCAUAAAAGGAGCUGGCACCUGCUCCUCACGAUGGGCACGUGGCCCCCCCUAUUUCAGAGACUAUGAAGGGCAGCCGUCGGGUGACCAGCUUUGCUGUGCCAGCAGUGGUCAGGGCUGGUCCCAGGACCCAGGAGCCUGUGUCACCAAGCAGCCGGCCCUAGCCAGCCUGGGACUUUCUGGAGGAUGUGUGCCAGCAUCUCUCAGAGGACACUUUCUUCCUCUCCAGGAGCCUCAGCCCCUUCCCACUUCCUUCAGCUCCCAGACUCAGGUCCACCUCCACCCUGCUCUGCACCUGGGGAACAGCGAGGAGUGGGAGGCUGGGCCGGGCACCCCCAGCUCCGUUCCUGGGCCCCAGCCCCAAGCACCGCUUGGCUCCCAUGGCCCUUGCUACUCACUCUGGGCCUGGCACCUCUACAGCCUCUUUUCCAAGCCCUCCCUCAGCCCCUGCCACCCGACGUGUGUCUGCUCCCCAGGACGGGACUUGGCUCUCACUUCUCUGCCUGCCGGCAUCUCCCACCCUUCCCAUGUCUCCGUCCUGAGCUGCCUCUUUCUCGUGCUCAUCCUGGGCAGUGAGGUCAUGGACCUGAGUGUGCCUGUCCUUUCUGCAUUCCCUGCGGUGCAGCGCGGUGUGUGGCUUUUUAUCCGAGUGCACCUGUUCCCCUGCAUUCCUGGGUGGCGUUCUUCUCCUUUCCCUUCUUGGACCUUCAAAGCACGAUUCUUCAGGUUCUUUCCAGGUCUUCGGGCCAGAUCUGUGGAAUCGUACUGUGAUUUCUCAGAAGCUUUGUUUCAUAAGACUGUUGGUUGUGUUAAAGGAGCAUGAUCUGUGAAGGUCGGUGACAAAAGAGGAAAGUGAAGGGAAGGGCACCCUGACACAUGGCUCCUGAGAGGGGCAUCCCCUCGGCAGCUGCAGAAGUGAGUGAGCGUAACUCCACUGCGAAGGGGUCUCAGCGUCUCUGAGCGGAGCUCCCCCAGCGCAGUUCCCCCAGCGCCACCUUGAAGGCGUGAGGGGCAUGGGGUCAGGGGGUGAGGAGGGGCCCUUUGGCCUAUUUGUGGGUGGACAGGAGCAUGCUGAGAAGCCCCUUCCUGCAUCUUUUUCUGUCUUCUGGUCAUCACCAGGGGAGGGAGAGGGUGCUGGCCACAAACCACUUGAUGCUGGGGGCUAACGGGAGCAGGUGUGGAGAGGGAAGCCCAUUGAGCUCUUUGCCUGGUGGAUGUUGCUAUGAAUUUUGGAUUUUGAUUAUACGAUGAUAAAAAUUACACAAAAAUGCAAAUGCUCUGCUAUUCAUUCAAAUAUGCAACAAAUAUUUGUGUACCCUCUAUGUGCCAGAUAUUAUGAAUGUUGUAUCUGCCAUCAUUUUUCUUAGAAAAUUAUUCAGCAUUUCUUAGGCUACGCACGAGCUUAGUUAUUCUUGACCUCCUAGGCAUACCCAAACAUUUAGUUAGUGCCUCAGGGCGCCUCAUCUCCAGGCCUCUGAUGUGCAGGCCCCCGGCCCCUGUGUUUUGUGGUCAGAGCACUCAGGAGCAGCCCCUUCGGUCUGAAUGCAUGCCAUGUGAGUGUCUCAUCUUUGCCAUUAGGUACAAGGGAUUCAUACACAUUUAACAGUUUAUAUAUUUAAUAGCUAUUUUUCUAAGACGCUUAGCACAAUGAACGCCAGCCACACAGGUCCCUGUGUGUUAAGGAUGAGUGGAGGCCUCCAUUUCCCACCCCCGUGCCCAAACCUGCAGUCAUGAUGCCUCUCUUGGGCGAGAUCCGAACCCUAGGGGGCUUUUUGGGGUCCUCAGUGCUUCUCUGCUACCUCACUUGUUUCUGCUGAAAUGGAAAACAAAGGAAGCUGUCUUCAGCAAUAGGAGGGUACCAAUUUGGUUUGAGGGCAAAGUGAAAGGUUCUUUGUGGCCCUAAAAACCACAGUAGGACCACUGAACUGUGGCUUUCCCAGGCCCCAGUGCAUGCAAAGUCCUUGACACUCGAGUUGGAAAAAGUGGGGUAUUAGGAGGAGGAAGUCUCAGCGCUCCUCUGUGGUCACUCACUGCUUCUCUCUCACUCCCUUUCUCCUUUUUCUCUCUCUGCGUCUCAGGCUUCAAGACCUCCGACAUCUGGAGGCUCCAUGCAAAUCCCACCAAACGUGUGAAACUGCCUCAGUAGCCCACACGAAGUAGAAUUGAUAGGAAGUAUGUGAGGGUUGAGGUGCACUGUGCUCAUAUGCAUUGUGCUCAUAGAUGGGAAAUUUUGUUUGUAAGCAUUCAAAUAUCAAUCGGAUUUUUUACUUUCAUAUUUUGGAGAAAAGAAUCUUUGCUCCAGUUCUUAUGUAUUUUUGGGAACCCUUGCAGAACUCAUAGACCCCAUAACCCUGGGGCACAGGGUUGGGGGUUAGACACCCCAAGGUCCUGUUUCCUGCUGAGGGACCUGGGCUAACGCCUCUGGCAACUCCUAUUUCAAGCUUUAAAUGAAGUGUUUCUUGGCUUCCCUUUCCUGCAUUUGCUGUUCACAGAGUCCCCACCACCUUCAACUGUCACCUCAUUUGCUCCACCAGGCACCGCUGAGAUGGUCAUCCUGCAAGAAAACUCUGAUAUUGUCACUCUUGUACAUAAAGACUCCUGUGGCAGCACUUGCUUACUGUGAGGUCCAGCAUGCGGCUGAGCCAGCAGGACUUUCACUUUCGGGUCUGACUCACAUCCUCUCUUGUGUCCCCAGCCACCCCGACCCCCAGUGUGGGCAUUCCCACUCAUCGCUCUGUCCCCUUCACAACCUUGUGUCCCCGGCCACCCAGGAUAGGGGCUCCUCCUGUGGGAUAGGGGCUCCUCCUGUGGGAUAGGGACUCCUCCUGUGGGAUAGGGGCUCCUCCUGUGGCAUAGGGACUCCUCCUGCAGGAUAUGAGCUCCUCUUACGGGAUAGGGACUCCUCCUGUGGGAUAGGGGCUCCUCCUGUGGGAUAGGGGCUCCUCCUGUGGGAUAGGGACUCCUAUGGGAUAGGG